GCUCUUGGGACCGGAAGUUAAGGCGUUCGCGGCGUGUGGUAAGUGAGGGGGGCGGGACGGGUGUACCGGGUUGUGGCGGCGAUGGCUGUCGGAGUUGGGCCGCUUGGGGGUAGUUUGGGGUGCGAGUCCAGGGGCGAGGGAAGUCUCGAGAUGAGGAGAAAUGUAGGAGGCAGCCGAAGGGCCGGCAAACGCGGACAGAGAUGGCACCUGAGCGUCCCUGGGAGAACCUGGGCGACAGGCCAGAGACCGAAAGAAAUGGAGGCACGAAAAGAAGCUUCGAGAAACUGAGGGACUGAAAGACGAGGGUGUUGGGAGAGGAGGGAAGCUGAAAACUAGAGAGCGUGGGCGAGAGUGCCGAUGGGUUCCAGCGAGAGUCUUAGAGCCCACGAGGCCGAGAGGCGUGGUCGCCCAUGAACUUGGGGAGUGGAGGGAAAAGUCGGAAACUGAUCGUGGACACUAGAAACAGAAAAAAUGGAAUUUAGAUGGAGAAACGAGACACUGAAUCACGGGGGAGACCGAGAGAUACGGAAGGAUGGAGACAGUUGAAAUAGGAAGAACCCCACAAAAGCUGGAGAUAAUGGAGAACGAUGCUGAGAAAUGGAAAAGCGAGGGAGUGGAGCCCGAACCCCUGGAUUUGAGUGGCUCAUGUAACACUCGGCUACUCACUUAGCCUCUCUAUUGCUCAGUAAAAUAGGGGGUGAUCAUAGUGCCUGACAGUCGUGAGAAAAGUGUGUGUGUGUAUGUACAUAGGUGUGGGAUAGGAAUAGAUCAUGCAGAUAGGAUAGGUCUGUGUGUUAAUGUGAGUAAGUAAGCAUGAGCUAUUACUAAAGCUUCUGAUAUUGGGAGAUAAAGUAUUAGAUGGGGAAAUGGAGAGAGGUGGUGAUGGAGAGUGAAUACUGGAAGGACAAAAGGGAGGAAAAAAAGAUUCAAACAGAAAAUGAGAAAGGGCGUGGUGACUCACUCCUGUCAUCCACAGCACUUUGGGAGGCUGCGGUGGGAGGAUCACUUGAGCUUGGGAGGUCGAGGCUGCUGUACGCCGUGAUUGUGCCACUGCACUUCAGGCUGGGUGACAGAGUGAGACCCUGUUUCAAAAAAACAAAAAUGAAUUUUUUUUUUUUUUUUUUGAGAUGGAGUUUCGCUCUUGUUGCCCAGGCUGGAGUGCAGUGGUGCGAUCUUGGCUCACUGCAACCUCUGCCUCCUGGGUUCAAGCGAGUCUCCUGCCUCAGCCUCCAGAGUAGCUGGGAUUACAGGCAGGUGCCACCACCCUGGCUAAUUUUGUAUUUUUAGUAGAGACGGGAUUUUUCCAUGUUCGUCAGGCUGGUCUCGCACUCCCGACCUCAGGUGAUCUGCCUGCCUCAGCCUCCCAAAGUGCUGGGAUUAUAGGCGUGAGCCACCAUGCCCGGCCUGAAAAAGCAUUUUUUUUUUAAUGAGAAAGAUGGAGAAAGUCAAAUGGAGAACUGAAGAGAGAUGGAGAAAGGAAGAGUUGGAUUACAGAGAAAAAUCAGACUACAGAAUGACUCAUAAGUGAAGAGAGAUGCGAGCUGACUAGGACAGGGAAGAGAGAUGAGGGUGAUGAUGAACAAGACGGACUGAAAAAGAGACAGAGGCCUGAAGAUGGAGUGGAGAGAGAUGGAGGGGACAGAGGGGGAAACAAACCCACUGAAGGCCAUGAGCCCAGGGCAAAUAGGCCAAGAGACCAAAAGAUGGUCAGAGACACAGUUAUACAGAAACUAGAAGAUGCAGACAAUCUAGAAGCCAAAAAAGAUAGAUACCUUGAGAGGAGCGGGAUGCUGUCAGUGGGGCCCAGCAUGCAUAAGCAGUUUCUAGCCUCAGAAGAAUGCUCUCAUUUUCUUUUUCUUUUUUUUUUUUUUUUUUUUUUUUUGAGACAGAGUCUCGCUCUGUUGCCCAGGCUGGAGUGCAGUGGCUCAGUCUUGGCUUCCUGCAAGCUCUGCCUCCAGGGUUCGAGUGAUUCUCCUGCCUCAGCCUCCCGAGUCGCUGGGACUACCCGAGUAGCCAGGUGCCCGCCACCACACCUGGCUAAUUUUUUUUCUCCAGCCUGGGUGACAGAGCAAGACUCCAUCUCAAAACAAAAAAGACUCCAACUGUAAGCAAAAAGGCAUUUUCUGGUGUAGCUGAGAAGUGGGGGGUUGAAGGGAACUAAGCUUCAAGACCUAAAUGAUGUUGCCAAGCUUCUCUUCCUCUCCCUCUUUCACCUCUCCCUGUGGUGCAGUGACCAUUCUUGUGCCUGUAUCUAGUUAUUUCUCUAGGAUAGAUUUUAGGAAAGACUCUGUCAUGUUCCAGAGCUACCACAAAGAGCUCCAGGCUUAUAUCAAACUUGCCUGAUUAUGAUGGAUAAAAUGAGAGCUUUUCUGUCCUAGCAACCGAGUGUAAAUUCCACAAAAGGGCCCUGAUUGGCCCUUCUUGGAUCAUGUGUCCGCUUCUCAGGCCAAUCCUUGGUUAGAGGGGGAGUAGACUACUAAGACUGGCCAGGUCUUUGUUACUUGCCUACCCAAUAGGGGUUCUUUGUCUUAAAGGCCCUCAGAACCAUGUAGAAUCGAGGAAGGGCUGUUGUCCAAAGGAAGGUGGAUACUGUCCUCAGAAAAGAAGUAAAGGGUUGUGCCAGGCAGGCAAAAAUUACAUAUAACACUUGCAAAAUUUUGCCUUUUAUCUCAAUGUUCUGAAUCUCACUGGACCCCGGGUGAAGAACCCUUGCCUUAUUCUUUUCAUUAUAUCACACCUCUCUCCUAUUACUGCCUGUGGAGACAAGGUUCUGCUGUUGGUUGGCCAUGUGACCUACAUCUCUCCUUUAGGUCUCAGGUGAAACAUCCCCUCCUCCCAGGAUCCUUCCCUGAUUCCCAAGCAUGGGAAGGAGGAGGAACCUCCUUUGGUGUCCCACAGCUCCCUAGGAUUCUGUUAUCACAGUCCCCAUCACUGGAUUGUCACAGUCUGAUGACGUGUGUGUCACAUGAGAGAUCAUGUGAUCAUGGCCGUCUGUGAGGACUCUGGUAGUCAUAUUCAUUACCUCCUUUUUCUAGUUCAGUGCUUAAGAAACAGGCUGUUAGAAAUGUUUCUAAAAAUGGGCUGGGCAUGGUGGCUCACACUGGUAAUCCCAACACUUUGGGAGGCUAAGGUGGGGGAAUUGCUUGAGCCCAGAAGUUUGAUAUCAACCUGGGCAACAUAGUGAGAUCUCAUCUCUACAAACAGUAAAAAAUUAGCUGGGUGUGGUGGCAUGUGCCUGUAGUCCCAGCUGCUCGGGAGGCUGAGGCGGGAGGAUCGCUUGAGUCCAGGAGGUCGAGGCUGUGGUGAGCCAUGAUUACGGCACUGCACUCCAGCCUGGGAAACAGAGUGAGACCCUGCCUCAAAAAGAAAAAAACAAAACAAAACCAAAAAAAGCAAUGUUCCCAAAAGAGAAUUAAUGUCUUCUGUUCUCUCUCUUAAGAAUCCAGGGCCUGAAAACCCAGAAUGAACUUGUGUCCAUCCCAGAGAUCACUGCAGAUGUCAUGAGGUACCCUUUGUGUCACCAGCUCAAGCAGGCCUCUGGCCACUUUAUCAUCUGUGGUGGUCCUGUGCCGUGACCAGGAGGAAAAAUUAGCUCUUUGAAGAGAAAGUAGUUCUCUAUUGCAGGCACUGGCCUCUUAAAUUGUUGCAGGUGGGGAAUGGAUGAGAAUAUUUGUUUUGGGUGAUCAGAACUGAGACUCCUAUUGUGGAUUAGUAACAUGCCUCCUCCUAGAACAAGGGAGGGCAGGGAUCGCCGAGACCACCACCGGGCUCCCAGCGAGGAAGAGGCCUUGGAGAAAUGGGACUGGAAUUGUCCAGAGACGCGUCGCCUCUUGGAAGAUGCCUUCUUCCGUGAAGAGGAUUACAUCCGUCAGGGUUCUGAGGAAUGUCAGAAGUUUUGGACCUUCUUUGAACGCCUGCAGAGAUUCCAGAAUCUCAAGACCUCCAGGAAGGAGGAGAAAGACCCUGGACAGCCCAAGCACAGCAUCCCAGCGCUGGCCGACCUACCUCGCACUUACGACCCACGUUACCGCAUCAACCUCUCUGUUCUUGGCCCUGCCACGCGGGGCUCUCAGGGACUGGGCAGGCACUUGCCCGCGGAGAGAGUGGCUGAGUUCCGCCGAGCCCUGUUGCACUACCUGGACUUUGGCCAGAAGCAGGCAUUUGGGCGUCUGGCCAAGCUGCAGCGUGAGCGGGCAGCCCUCCCCAUCGCCCAGUAUGGGAACCGCAUCCUGCAGACGCUGAAGGAGCACCAGGUGGUGGUAGUGGCCGGUGACACCGGCUGUGGCAAGUCCACUCAGGUGCCCCAGUACCUGCUGGCUGCUGGCUUCAGUCAUGUGGCGUGCACCCAGCCCCGGCGGAUCGCCUGCAUCUCACUGGCCAAGCGUGUGGGCUUUGAGAGCCUCAGUCAGUAUGGCUCACAGGUCGGCUACCAGAUCCGCUUUGAGAGCACACGUUCGGCGGCCACCAAGAUUGUAUUCCUGACAGUGGGGCUGCUCCUGCGACAAAUCCAGCGGGAACCCAGCCUGCCCCAGUAUGAGGUCCUGAUUGUGGAUGAAGUCCAUGAGCGGCAUCUCCACAACGAUUUCCUCCUGGGCGUCCUCCAGCGCCUGUUGCCCACGCGGCCUGACCUCAAGGUCAUCCUCAUGUCGGCCACCAUCAACAUCUCGCUCUUCUCCAGCUAUUUCAGCAAUGCCCCUGUGGUACAGGUGCCUGGGAGGCUGUUCCCCAUCACGGUUGUGUACCAGCCGCAGGAGGCGGAGCCGACCACGUCCAAGUCAGAGAAGCUGGACCCGCGGCCUUUCCUGAGGGUGCUGGAGUCCAUUGACCACAAGUACCCGCCUGAGGAGCGGGGUGACCUCCUCGUCUUCCUCAGCGGCAUGGCGGAGAUCAGCGCCGUGCUGGAGGCUGCCCAGACCUAUGCCAGCCACACCCAGCGCUGGGUGGUACUGCCACUGCACAGCGCCCUGUCUGUGGCCGACCAGGACAAGGUAUUUGAUGUGGCACCCCCUGGAGUCCGGAAAUGCAUCCUCUCCACCAACAUUGCUGAGACCUCAGUCACCAUUGACGGGAUCCGCUUCGUAGUAGAUUCCGGAAAGGUGAAGGAGAUGAGCUACGAUCCGCAGGCCAAGCUGCAACGGCUGCAGGAGUUCUGGAUUAGUCAGGCCAGCGCAGAGCAGCGGAAGGGCCGGGCGGGCCGCACGGGCCCCGGAGUCUGCUUCCGCCUCUAUGCCGAAUCGGACUAUGAUGCCUUCGCCCCCUACCCCGUCCCAGAAAUUCGGAGGGUGGCCCUGGACUCGUUGGUGCUGCAGAUGAAGAGCAUGAGUGUGGGGGACCCCCGAACCUUCCCCUUCAUCGAGCCCCCACCACCAGCCAGCCUGGAAACCGCCAUCCUCUACCUCCGGGACCAGGGGGCCCUGGACAGCUCAGAGGCCCUCACACCCAUUGGGUCCCUGCUAGCCCAGCUGCCUGUGGACGUUGUGAUUGGGAAGAUGCUGAUCCUGGGCUCCAUGUUCAGCCUGGUGGAGCCUGUGCUCACCAUCGCAGCCGCACUUAGCGUCCAGUCGCCCUUCACCCGCAGCGCCCAGAGCAGCCCAGAGUGCGCGGCAGCACGGCGGCCGCUGGAGAGCGACCAGGGUGACCCCUUCACGCUCUUCAACGUCUUCAACGCCUGGGUGCAGGUGAAAUCUGAACGGAGCAGAAACUCUCGCAAGUGGUGCCGCCGCCGGGGCAUAGAGGAGCAUCGACUGUACGAAAUGGCCAACCUUCGGCGCCAGUUCAAGGAGCUGUUGGAGGACCACGGGCUGCUGGCUGGGGCCCAGGCCGCGCAGGUAGGGGACAGCUACAGUCGGUUGCAGCAGCGCCGGGAGCGCCGGGCCCUGCACCAGCUGAAACGCCAGCACGAGGAGGGCGCGGGGCGCAGGCGCAAGGUGCUGCGGCUGCAGGAGGAGCAGGACGGCGGCUCCAGUGACGAGGACAGGGCUGGCCCAGCCCCCCCAGGGGCCAGUGAUGGCGUGGACAUCCAGGAUGUGAAGUUCAAGCUUCGGCAUGACCUGGCGCAGCUGCAGGCCGCUGCCAGCUCAGCCCAGGACCUGAGCCGCGAGCAGCUGGCUCUGCUGAAGCUGGUGCUGGGCCGGGGCCUGUACCCACAGCUGGCCGUCCCCGACGCCUUCAACAGCAGCCGAAAGGACUCAGACCAGAUUUUCCACACGCAGGCCAAGCAGGGCGCCGUGCUGCACCCCACCUGCGUCUUCGCUGGCAGCCCCGAGGUGCUGCACGCACAGGAGCUGGAGGCCAGCAACUGCGACGGAAGCCGAGACGACAAGGACAAGAUGAGCAGCAAACACCAGCUCCUCAGCUUCGUGUCCCUGCUGGAGACCAACAAGCCGUACCUGGUGAACUGCGUCCGCAUCCCUGCCCUCCAGUCCCUCCUGCUUUUUAGCCGGUCUUUGGACACCAAUGGUGACUGCUCCCGCCUGGUGGCCGAUGGCUGGCUGGAGCUGCAGCUAGCAGACAGUGAAAGUGCCAUCCGACUCCUGGCGGCUUCCCUGCGGCUCCGUGCCCGCUGGGAAAGUGCCCUGGACCGGCAGCUGGCGCACCAGGCCCAGCAGCAGCUGGAGGAGGAGGAGGAGGAUACGCCAGUCAGCCCCAAGGAGGUGGCCACCCUGAGCAAGGAACUCCUGCAAUUCACGGCAUCCAAGAUUCCUUACAGCCUCCGGCGGCUCACAGGGCUAGAAGUCCAGAACAUGUAUGUGGGACCCCAGACCAUCCCAGCCACCCCCCAUCUUCCUGGCCUCUUUGGCAGCUCCACCCUGUCCCCCCACCCCACAAAGGGGGGCUACGCAGUCACUGACUUCCUCACCUACAACUGCCUCACGAAUGACACAGACCUGUACAGCGACUGUCUCCGAACCUUCUGGACCUGCCCCCACUGUGGCCUGCAUGCGCCCCUCACGCCCCUGGAGCGCAUCGCCCAUGAGAACACCUGCCCCCAGGCCCCACAGGAUGGGCCCCCAGGGGCUGAGGAAGCUGCCCUCGAAACCCUCCAGAAGACAUCUGUCCUGCAGAGGCCCUACCACUGCGAGGCCUGCGGGAAGGACUUCCUCUUUACACCCACAGAGGUGCUGCGCCACCGGAAGCAGCACGUGUGAGCUGGGCCAGGAGCCCUGCCCACCUCCGUGCAGCUGACCUGCCCUCCAGCCCAGGACUAGGGGCAGGACUCUUGCCUGAACCCCCAGCCUGGGCUUAGCCCUGUGGUCCUGUCCCAGUGCAGAGGGCCUGGAGCACGGAUUGUGAAUAAAGCCUCACAUGCUGAUACACACUGUUAGGCCUGCACCUGCCCAUCCAGAAAGCAGCAGCUGCCUUGUUAGUCCUCCCCAGGGUCUAGCUUUCCUUCUUCCUGCUGCAGGGUGCUGCCUGAGGGGUCCUGGGUAGGAGGGGCGUUAGAGCCAGCAGGGACCUCCCAUGUCUCCAGAUUCCAGGUGCAGGUUCUUAGCACCUCCGCAGCCGCUCUCUCUUGAGUCCAUCCUCAGUCUCUCCUACCCCUUGAAGUAGGGGGACCCUGAAUUUGCCCAUCCACCUGGGUCACUUUGAGAGUUGUGCAGGGGGGCUGGGAGCACUGGUGUUCACGUGGGACCACAGGCUGCACCAUAAGACCCACUCACAAUAAAAAAAUAAAAGGCCGAGCCGGGCAUGGUUGCUCACUCCCGUAAUAAAAAAAUAAAAGAACAGGCUGAGCCGGG